AGCGAUGCGUCCAGGGUCCCACAGGGAGCCAAGGCUGGACAGAUGGGCAGGCUGGGUGGGGCCAGGAAGGCCACGGCUGUUUCCAGCUGUUGCAGAUGUGCUGCCUCCGGGGUCCGUGCAAACUCCUUUCCGCCUGCAGGCUGGCGAAGGGGCCAGGGCACACAGCAGGGGAGUUAGACUUGGCAGCCCCUUGACCCCAGACUGCCUUCAUCAAUGGAGCAGGAGCUGCCCAGAACCCUUUUCCUGUUCUCCCACAUUCAGGGGCAUGAGCCCCCUUGGCCCAGUCCUGGAACAGGGCACCCCGGGAGGGCCCCUCAGGAAGAGGCCGGGGCUGCGGCUUCGGGUGGGGCCGGCAGCCUCUGCUGAGAGCCCAGCAUCUGGAAGCCAUCAGGCCAGGGGCGGGGGGAGUUGCAGGGGAGGUCCAGGGAGGGGGACAUGCCUCCUCCAGGCCACACACAAGCCCAACCCUCGGGAGCGUGGCCUUGGGCCCACAACCGCUGCCUCUGCACCCUGGCCCGCAGCCCCGCCCCCUGGCGCACACGCCCCGCCCUCGUCCGAAGCCACGCCCCCAGCCAGCAGCCACGCCCUCUUCCCCCAGGCUGCCUUCUCACCGCACUGGCCACUGCUCCUGCAAGGGUCAGCAGCGCUCCCCACAGCAUGGUGGGAGCCUCGCUUCUCCGGCGCAGGCCUUGCCAACAUUCCACUAACCCCCGAGACUCAGCGGGACCAGGAGCGGCGGAUUCGGCGGGAGAUCGCCAACAGCAACGAGCGGAGACGCAUGCAGAGCAUCAACGCGGGAUUCCAGUCCCUCAAGACCCUCAUCCCCCACACAGACGGAGAGAAGCUCAGCAAGGCAGCCAUUCUCCAGCAGACAGCCGAGUACAUCUUCUCCCUGGAGCAGGAGAAGACCAGGCUCUUGCAGCAGAACACACAGCUCAAGCGCUUCAUCCAGGAGCUGAGCGGCUCGUCCCCCAAGCGACGGCGGGCAGAGGACAAGGACGAAGGCAUAGGCUCCCCGGACAUCUGGGAGGACGAGAAGGCGGAGGACCUGCGGCGGGAGAUGAUUGAGCUGCGGCAGCAGCUGGACAAGGAGCGCUCGGUGCGCAUGAUGCUGGAGGAGCAGGUGCGCUCGCUGGAGGCCCACAUGUACCCGGAAAAGCUCAAGGUGAUUGCGCAGCAGGUGCAGCUGCAGCAGCAGCAGGAACAGGUGAGGCUGCUGCACCAGGAGAAGCUGGAGCGGGAACAGCAGCAGCUGCGGACCCAGCUUCUGCCCCCUCCGGCCCCCACCCACCACCCCACGGUGAUCGUGCCAGCACCGCCUCCUCCUCCCUCCCACCACAUCAAUGUCGUCACCAUGGGCCCCUCCUCGGUCAUCAACUCUGUUUCCACAUCCCGGCAAAAUCUGGACACCAUCGUGCAGGCAAUCCAGCACAUCGAGGGCACCCAGGAAAAGCAGGAGCUGGAGGAGGAGCAGCGGCGAGCUGUCAUCGUGAAGCCUGUCCGCAGCUGCCCGGAGGCCCCCACCUCUGACACCGCCUCCGACUCCGAGGCCUCAGACAGUGACGCCAUGGACCAGAGCCGGGAGGAGCCGUCGGGGGACGGGGAGCUUCCCUGACUACCCCCCCAGCCCUCCUCUCCCUUCUGGGGGCUGGAGGGAGCCGGGGCAGCCACAGGGAGAGACAUGGGCGAAUGAGUGAGAAAUUUUUACAAAAUUACGAUGUCAUUUGGGUCUCUUUUAUGACCUCUUUUUCAAUACUGUAAAUCGACCUUUGAACGAAGCCACUCAACCCGAGGUCCCGGGGCUGGGGUGUCGCAGAGCGUGUGGGAGCAUCGGCACCCCAGGGCGGGGCCUCGGCCCCGGGGGCUGGAGGAAGCUGACACGGAGAUGCCUGGCCUCUCUCUGCCAAAAAGCAUUUUUUCCUUUAAAUAUGUUUUUUAAGAACAGGGAAAAUUAAACAAAACCCCAGGUUAUUUCUUCCCUGCCCAGAGCCAGCCUGGGAUUGUCAGCCUUCAAUCCCCUUUCCUUCCUCUUUUUGGGUUUUCUUCUUUCUCCUUUAAGCACUUACAUGGUUGGGGGUAAGACUAGGCUGGGGCAUUCUGGGGGCCCGGAGGUCUCCGUUGCUUCUUGGUUGGGGUUUGCUGCUGCUGUGCCCCCCUCCCCCUUCCCCAUCUCGGCACUAGAAUUCGCCACUCUCCCACCCCCCAGCCCCCACCUCUGCCUCCAGGUCUCAUCUUCCACCCCAAAAAUGUCUGUCUCUCUCUUUUUGUUUUGUUUGUUGUUGGUUUUUUAUUUCUUUUUGGUUUGCUUUCUGUUUUUGUUUUGUUUUUCUUUUUUUUCUUUCUUUUUUUUUUUUUUUUACAAUUUUGAGGUCUUCGUGUUCAAGGAGAAGCUAUUAUAUUUUGUUAAGAAAGUGGGGAGAAAAAAACCAAGAGGCCACCGUGCCUUUGUAAAGAAACAAAAUAAAGUUUGUACUUUGUUUUUUA